CAGUAUGUGGAAGAACUAGAAGAACCCAGGAGUUGUGAUCCUAAACAACUUUUAACUGGGCCUUGUUAUGAUUUCCACGUGUGAUACUUUACUCAUUCUGAGAUUAACAGUCGCACUGGUGAAACUGACAGCCGCUAUAUGGCCAUACUAAUGUAACUUAUUACAAGACAGGAAGUGAGAAGAGUUGUUUGAUCUAGUUGAAACCAUGGGGGAAUUUGGGAAAGCAGAGUAAAUUUGCUAAUUUGGAAGUCUGAGACUUCAGAGCUUGUUAUUCUUGAAGCAGUUGUUAAAAGUCAGUGGACAUCCUGAUUCUCAGGUCUCCGAUGUGGAUGUGCAUCCUCUCCGGCAGCAUGAUUUUUCCAGGACCAGAAUGUGACAGGAGCGGCCCCGCAAUAGAAUUGCAGGCUCACAGGCCGGCUGCAGCACUUGGCUGUAUUGCGAGGCUCCUUUCCAGCUGCUUAGUUCACAUGAUGCCUGGUUUAUAAAACCUAGUGAAGUGUUUUAUUUUUUAAAAAUAAAUCACUUUUGGGAAGGAAAUGUGUGACUUUUUCUUCUUUUAAAUUAUCAUUCAAAAUGAGAAUUUUCCUCUUAAAGAGGAAAUCUUUUUGUUUUAGGAAUACAUUCCUGACUCUUAGGUGACCCGGGUAUUGGAAUCUUGUGGAUAAUUGACGUUAUCUAAUGUAAUUUAGACUCUAGUAGAGUCUGUUCAGUUUUGGAUGUCAAAGAAAUGGAAAGAUGGUGAAACAACCUGGAAACCAUACCUUAUCAUGAACAGCGGAAGUAUCUUGAAAGUGUGGCCCUGAGAAGAAAAAAACUGAGGAUUAUUUUGGAGUCUGUUCAGAGCCAGUGAUCAAAGACAAUGUAGUUGUGGUUUAUGAGGUAUUGGAAGAGAUGCUUGACAAUGGUUUUCCAUUGGCUACCGAGUCGAACAUUCUUAAAGAACUCAUAAAGCCUCCUACCAUCCUUCGAACGGUUGUCAACACCAUCACAGGAAGCACGAAUGUGGGUGACCAGCUUCCCACUGGGCAGCUGUCAGUGGUGCCUUGGCGACGGACUGGGGUGAAAUAUACCAACAAUGAGGCCUAUUUUGAUGUGAUUGAAGAGAUUGAUGCAAUUAUUGAUAAAUCAGGCUCCACAAUUACUGCUGAGAUCCAGGGGGUGAUUGAUGCCUGUGUCAAGCUGACUGGCAUGCCAGACCUUACACUUUCCUUCAUGAACCCUAGGUUGUUGGAUGAUGUCAGCUUCCAUCCUUGUGUUCGUUUCAAACGCUGGGAAUCUGAGCGCAUCCUCUCCUUCAUCCCUCCUGAUGGAAACUUCCGCCUGCUGUCUUACCAUGUCAGUGCACAGAAUCUGGUUGCAAUCCCAGUGUAUGUCAAACAUAACAUCAGUUUCCGGGACAGUAGUUCCCUUGGACGCUUUGAAAUAACGGUGGGACCCAAGCAGACGAUGGGGAAGACCAUUGAGGGAGUGACUGUCACCAGCCAGAUGCCCAAGGGGGUCCUGAACAUGAGCCUUACUCCAUCACAGGGGACACACACAUUCGACCCAGUCACAAAGAUGCUGUCUUGGGAUGUAGGAAAAAUAAAUCCACAAAAGCUACCAAGUUUGAAGGGGACCAUGAGUCUUCAGGCUGGAGCUUCCAAACCAGAUGAAAACCCCACAAUUAACCUGCAGUUUAAGAUCCAGCAGCUGGCCAUUUCUGGACUCAAGGUGAAUCGUCUGGAUAUGUAUGGAGAAAAGUACAAACCCUUUAAGGGCAUAAAAUACAUGACCAAAGCUGGGAAGUUCCAAGUUCGAACCUGAAGGGAGCAUUUGCUGAGGGAAUAGUCUUGCACAUUUUUUCAUUUCUUACUUGUCUAAAAGUAAAAAAAAAUAUCAGCCUGUCUCCUAGGUCAGUCCCCUCCUGGACCCACCCGCUCCCUUUUUUCCUUAGCCUUCAGUGCCAUGGAACUAAUCAAGGGAGGAAAAGGUCACCAGGGAGAACUGGACAGAACUGAAACACAGCAACACCAGUUCUCAAGGACAAGGUGUGUGAUGGGGGUAGGAAGCUUGGUGCUUAUGUAACCAUUUUAAACGUGGUUUCUAUAGGAAAGACCAACAUUUGUUUAGCUUGCUUGGCUUUAAUUAUCUAAAGCCAAUGAAAGACUUCUUUGUUGAUUUUUUAAGAUAGAAAGAUUAAAAAGAAAGAAAGAUGGGAAGAAAAUGAAUGUCAGUCAAGGAAAGGCCACUUAAGGAUCUGCUCUAUGAAGGAGAAGAAAGAGGAAAAAGAAGUAAAGGAGUUAGGAGGAGACACUUAAAUGAAAGAUUGGCAAGAAAAGCAGUCGGACUCUACCUUAAGGAGGGAUGGGAAGGAAAGAGUUGAGUUGGUUUCUUUCUGAUUCCUCUACUCAUGUAGAAAACACUUGUACUUCUGGAAAUGGACUGGAGACUUUUUAAAUUUGAGUCCACUAUUGACAUGGAAACCCCAGUGGAAUCAGAUUUUCCCUCAAAGACCAUGAUGGUAUCGGACUAGUUUUCAGACACUGCCUGUUGCUGUCCAUCAGCACUUGGUCUCUUAUCUUCAGUGAGAAGGUGACCCGCCUUCUUCCCAUGGUGGCUGCCUAAAGUGCUUCUUUUCUAACCCAAAACAGUUCUACUCACUUCCUUUUACAGAAUUCACCGGCCAUUUUCCUGUUACCUGAUCCUUCUACAGGAUUUUUAAAAAGUAAGAGAGUUUCAGAGAAGCCGAUCCCAUAAUCCCCAGUGCAGCCAGGGUUUGUGUGUCAUCGUACUGGAGUAGAGGGCCGACUCUUCCCAUGAAGGUGAGCACAGCUGUGAGUGAGUGAGCUCAUAUCUCCAUUUGUCAGUGCUGGACUGGUACCAGAUCGUAACCUUCCCGUUGGUCGGAAACUUUUCCAUCUGUCGCCCUAGAAAAAGAGAAAGCUUACCAUCGAGGGUGUGGUUGAUCCUUGAAGCUGCUUGGUAAAGUUAUCAUUUCCUCAGUCUUUUCUUUUGUACUCCUAUCAUGUAUUCAUUAAUAUCUACCAGUCCCUUUUCAUUCUAAGACAAAACAUUUCUCCUAAAUCUCUGAAUAAAAUCAGUGCUGUAGGAAGAUGGACUGUGUUGAUCAUGGGUGUAAGCAACCCAGUUUAAGAAACAUGGCAACUAAAGGGAUACCUCAGGCUUUCUUUCCCAGUGGGUCAUUUUUGUCCUAGUUCAGUGUGUCUGUUACUAUUUAAAUAUUUAUACAAAAGGGUUUUUGUUUAUAGCUUAAGGAAUGAUACUGUGCUCUGCUUGGUGCAUGGAGAAAAAGGAAGACCCGUACUCUCCACACCCUAGAGCUUUUCUCUAAAUAUUGUGCAAAGUUUUUGCUAGUUUUAUCUUCUGACUUUGGGACUAGUUUUUGCUGCAGAGUUGUGUUGCUUUGUGAUUUUCCUCUGGGAUAGUGUACUGUACACAACCAGAUGUGUUCCACACUCCGUGACUCCGCAGUUUGUCCUGGAGUGACAUACACAUCCACCAUGGAAAGGGAAGCAUCUCUGCCUGUGGAUUCUCAAGUACUUGGAAGCACCUCUCCUGAGGAACCUACAGGAUUCUAAGGUUUCCUAGGUCACUGAACAACUAAUCUUGGUCCCUGAAUAUUUCUAGGUUUGUAAGUGCAGCAGUUUUAUUUCCUCUAGAACUCAUCCUGUUUCAAGGGAAGUACCUAAGAAGAUAUAGAGUGUUUCUAGGGUAAGGGACCUGCAGGUGUAAGCAUAGAUGAAAUAACUGUCCUGUCACAUGUGCAGCAGGCCAUGGAGUGUAGCGGGCAUCGCUGCCGCCAUUCCUGCAGCAUCACCAUAAGCAGUGCAGGGUGUCUCCAUCGAGCUGUUUGGUUCCAUGUGUGUUUAACAUGUGCAGAAGUAGCUUCUCUGUUUAAGUUUAAUAAAGUUGAGUUUCACCAGUC